CUUAUUUCUUAUGAAUGUCGGAUAGCUGCACCAGCUUGGUGGGGAAAGGGUUUGAUGAAUAGCACAAAGACACUGGCUGUUCCCUGGAGGCUGUCCCUUUAAAGGAGAAUCUUAGUUUAUUCUGGGGGGAGGGGAUGCACACAUUAGAGUAGGAAAGAGGGCUUGGAAUAAAAUGAAAACACUCCCCCUUCAUAGUCAUUGUACUGAAAUGCAAAGACUGCUUCCUAAGCUGGAGAUGCUAACCUUGGGUAGCUCCUUCUGUUCUCUUCAAGGGGAAUUUUGUCAGGCUAUGGAUUCAUUUACAACUGUUAGUCAUGUGGGCAUGUGUGAGGAAACAGAUGCCAGUUUUAAUGUAUUUAGCCCGAAGUUCCAAUUUGAUAGGAGCCACUGUCAGUCUCUGAGGUUCCACCAAAAUAUGGAACUUGAUUUUGGACACUUUGACGAAAGAGAUAAGACAUCCAGGAACAUGCGAGGCUCCCGGAUGAAUGGGUUGCCUAGCCCCACUCACAGCGCCCACUGUAGCUUCUACCGAACCAGAACCUUGCAGGCACUGAGUAAUGAGAAGAAAGCCAAGAAGGUACGUUUCUACCGCAAUGGGGACCGCUACUUCAAGGGGAUUGUGUACGCUGUGUCCUCUGACCGUUUUCGCAGCUUUGACGCCUUGCUGGCUGACCUGACGCGAUCUCUGUCUGACAACAUCAACCUGCCUCAGGGAGUGCGUUACAUUUACACCAUUGAUGGAUCCAGGAAGAUCGGAAGCAUGGAUGAACUGGAGGAAGGGGAAAGCUAUGUCUGUUCCUCAGACAACUUCUUUAAAAAGGUGGAGUACACCAAGAAUGUCAAUCCCAACUGGUCUGUCAACGUAAAAACAUCUGCCAAUAUGAAAGCCCCCCAGUCCUUGGCUAGCAGCAACAGUGCACAGGCCAGGGAGAACAAGGACUUUGUGCGCCCCAAGCUGGUUACCAUCAUCCGCAGUGGGGUGAAGCCUCGGAAGGCUGUGCGUGUGCUUCUGAACAAGAAGACAGCCCACUCUUUUGAGCAAGUCCUCACUGAUAUCACAGAAGCCAUCAAACUGGAGACCGGGGUUGUCAAAAAACUCUACACUCUGGAUGGAAAACAGGUAACUUGUCUCCAUGAUUUCUUUGGUGAUGAUGAUGUGUUUAUUGCCUGUGGUCCUGAAAAAUUUCGCUAUGCUCAGGAUGAUUUUUCUCUGGAUGAAAAUGAAUGCCGAGUCAUGAAGGGAAACCCAUCAGCCACAGCUGGCCCAAAGGCAUCCCCAACACCUCAGAAGACUUCAGCCAAGAGCCCUGGUCCUAUGCGCCGAAGCAAGUCUCCAGCUGACUCAGCAAACGGAACCUCCAGCAGCCAGCUCUCUACCCCCAAGUCUAAGCAGUCUCCCAUCUCUACGCCCACCAGUCCUGGCAGCCUCCGGAAGCACAAGGACCUGUACCUGCCUCUGUCCUUGGAUGACUCGGACUCGCUUGGUGAUUCCAUGUAAAGGAGGGGAGAGUGCUCAGAGUCCAGAGUACAAAUCCAAGCCUAUCAUUGUAGUAGGGUACUUCUGCUCAAGUGUCCAACAGGGCUAUUGGUGCUUUCAAGUUUUUAUUUUGUUGUUGUUGUUAUUUUGAAAAACACAUUGUAAUAUGUUGGGUUUAUUUUCCUGUGAUUUCUCCUCUGGGCCACUGAUCCACAGUUACCAAUUAUGAGAGAUAGAUUGAUAACCAUCCUUUGGGGCAGCAUUCCAGGGAUGCAAAAUGUGCUAGUCCAUGACCUUUCAAUGGAAAGCUUAGGUGCCUGCGUUAUAUUUGCCCUGUCUAAUUUUGCCCAUACAGUCUUCCUUCUGUAGAGGGCUGUUUACAUAUACAGCACUUAAAAUGUUUGUGUGGGAAAAAAAAAACUCAUUGGCAGAUCCAAGAAUGACAAACACAAGUGCCCCUUUUCUCUGGAUCUCAAGAAUGGUGGAGGACCCUGGAAGGACAGCAAGGCAGCUCCCCAGCCUCACUCUUCACUCCUGAUUGAGGCCCGGGUUUGUUGUCCAGCACCAAUUCUGGCUGUCAAUGGGGAGAAAUAAACCAACAACUUAUAAUUGUGACACCAGAUGCUUAGGAUCCUGGUGCUGGGUUAGCUAAGAGAAUAGACAGAAUUGGAAAAUACUGCAGACAUUUCCGAAGAGUUUAUAAAGCACAGUGAAUUCCUGGUCAAUCUCUCCACUGAGGCAAUUUGGAAUCAAUAAGCAAUUGAUAAUAGUUUGGAGUAAGGGACUUCAUAUACCUGAUUCCUCUAGAAGGCUGUCUAACAUACCACAUGAUUACAUGAACUGUAUGGUAUCCAUCUAUCUCUGUUCUAUUGAAUGCCUUGUUAACAGCCAACACUGAAAACACUGUGAGAAUUUGUUUUCAGGUCUGACACCUUUCAGUCUCUUUUUAUAGCAAGAAAUCAAUAUCCUUUUUAUAAAAAUUCAUGUCUGUAUUUCAGGAGCAAACUCUUCAGGCUCCUUUUUUAUAAACUGGUGAUUUUUCUUUUGUCUAAAAAACACAUGAAGAAAAUUUACCAAAAAAAAAAAAAAAAGCAGAAGAAUAAUGUAGUUUAGAAAUUAUGCUGUCACUGCCAAACAGUAACCUCCAGGAGAAAACAAGAUGAAUAGCAGAGGCCAAUUCAAUAGAAUCAGUUUUUUGAUAGCUUUUUAACAGUUAUGCUUGCAUUAAUAAUUUCAAUGUGGACCAGACAUUCUAAUUAUAUUUUAAAUGAAAUGUUACAGCAUAUUUUAAGCAACUCUUUUUAUCUAUAAUCCUAAUAUUUCAUACUGAAGACACAGAAAUCUUUCACUUGUCUUUAACAUUAGAAAGGAUUUCUCUUUACUAAGGACUGAUCAUUUGAAAUAGUUUUCAGUCUUUUGAGAUACAGGUUUAUAACACUGCUUUUUUUUUUCUGUAAUCAUAGCCCAUAAUGGCAAAGACAACUAAAUUUAAGUGAAGGUCAUGCAUGCCAAUUCUGUGUUUGCUUUUAGCAGAUAUGAAGAUUUCCUUAUUUCUUUGUAAUUGUGCAGAUAUUUUGAAAGGCACAGCAUUCGAAGCCAAGCUGCUGUUUGGCUACUGAAUGGCUUGCAGUUGUUCCUCCACUCUAAAUGGAAUGAGCUUGCUGUGUGUGUGUGUGGUGGUGGUGGGAGGGGGUGGUGCAUGUGUGUGUGUGUGUGUGCAUCUGCAGCUGCUUCAAAAUUAGGAAAUACUACAGGACACCCCUGUAAUGGAUUGGUGGCAACUGGGUGGCACUGCUGAUGUGCACUGUGUAGGGGGGAACCCAGUGGUGGUGGGGUAGCUCAGAUGCCCCUAGACAAGCUUCAGAUGUCUGUAGCUACCAGAAACAUUUUCGGUUCAGGAAAAGUGAGAUGAUGGUAGUACUGGUUUCUGGUGAAAUUGAAGAACCCCAAAUGAUGAGGAUCUCUUUUUGCCCCCUCUCCUUUUUUUGUAGACCCAUUCAAAACCAUUAAUAAGCCCAUUUUACUAAGCCCCUAUUUCUUUCUAGAAGCUCAGGGUUUUCUUAGUGCCUCCCAGAACAUUUUGUAGUUAAUUGGGAAAAAGUGAUACUUGGAUUAGGGGGUGUGGGCAUAAAGAAUGGUGGGAGGCCUGAUUUUAAACUUCAGGCCAGAACCCCCAAUGACUCCACCCAUAGUCUCACUUUAGGUCUCAUUUAGUCCAUCACCUUUAUUUUAAGUUGAGGAAGUGGAGGCUGGUAAAGAGCAGGACCAGAGGAAGAAUCCAGAUUUCCUUAUGCUUGGGCCUCACACUAGCUCUCUGAGUAUUUCCUUGAUUGCGGUAUAUGUACUACUAGAAAAUACCAAAUGGAUAUAUUUUCUUUAGGAUAACCUUUGAACCAACAAUCUUCAAUAACAAUAGUACAUCUUCCAUCUUACUUUUAAUCGAGUAUAAGGAAAUGUUUCUUUAUGGCCAUUUUGGAGGGAGCAGGGGAUGAGGCUUGGCAUAGUCCAAAAUUUAAGUCUCCAAUAAUUAAUUGCAUUUUAAAUUGGCCCACUUUCAAGGCAAUUUUUUUUGUGUGUCUGUAACUGAGCUCCUCCACCCCUGUCAUUCACUUCCAAUUUUACCCAAUCCAAUUUUAGCACUCAAGUUCCAUUGUGUUAAUUUCUGCACGGUCAACAAACAUCAAGUCAGCAAGCAUUUGCCACCACUCCCUAUACUUCUCCCUCCUUCUUACACACACACACACACACACACACACAAUCCAUCUCUUGCUUGUUCCUACCUCCUGAUUUUUCUUCCCUACAGAAAUAGAAAUAGGGACAAAGAAGGGGAAAAUGUAUAUAUUGGGGCUGGGCUGAACAACUAACUUCAUAAGUAGUAUUAACUAGGGGUAAAUUGAGAGAAAAGCUCCUUUUCUCUUCACUGUUUUGGAAAGGAUAGCCAUUAGCAUGACUGCUUUGUGUCCUUAUGGACUUUAGUAUUAGCCUAGAUUGAAUUAUAGCGUUUUCUAGCUGGAAGGAACCUUAAGAUCACAUCAUCUACUCCUCUACUCCAAAUUUCUCAUUCUUCAGGCCAGGAAACCGAGACACAGAGGUAAAGUAAUUUCCCCAAGGUCACACAGCUGGCUGGGGCAGGAUUGGGUUUACAACCCACAUCUCCUGGCUCUUAUUCCAGGGCCUUUUCCCACUAAGUAGUAUUGCCUUCCAUUAGGCUCCUGAGAGUUAUUUCUCAGGGUCAUGUUGCAUCUUGGAGCCACAUGCUGCUGCCCUGAUCUCAGUGGGAAAUCCACCCAGCAACCUAAUACAGCCCCUUUUCCCUGCAUUCACCUGGUUCCCAUCCACAUGGGUUGCAGAUGUCCUUGAAGAGAGUGAGGCAUUGAGGGCCAAUAGGAGCAAUGGGGUCCCUGGCCUUGUCCAUCUGAUUCAGGAGAUCACUGCUCCAUCGUGAGGAGCCCUCUGAAUAGCCCCCCACUGAAUGCUUGCCUUGCCCAAAUGGAAUGGAGGAAGAUUGAUUUUCUCCAUCAGUUCACCUUGUGUCAUCUCAUAAUGGUUGGUCUUUCCAGGCUGAGGGAAAUGUUUCUUGUUUCCAGAGUAGAAAAAGAAAGAGUGGAACAAUAGCUUUGUUCAUCCUAACUUUCUGAGAUGGCUUUUCAACAUUUUAAAAAAACUAGUGUGGCUACCAUUCACUGGCAAUGAUUUCUUUUAGAAUAUGGGAGUAAGAUGAGCUAGAGAAAAUAACCUGGUCUCACUGUGGUUGCCCUCAUCCACAAUGUCCCCAAAGCCAUCCUGCUCUGAUGAGGACAAUUUCCAGGUAUAAGCAAGGGGCUUUGUGACAAAAAUGUACCCUGGCUGAUGUUAAACAUUGGCUCCUGUGUUUGCACCAAAAUAGCAAGCUGUGUGCUCUAUACACUCUUCCCAUCGUCUUGUGUACACUGCUCCUGUGGCCUUCCACAGCAGAAACCAGGGCAAAAGGGUCCAAACACAUGGUUUUCCUUGCUGCAAGGCUCUUCCUGGGAACUAAGGGGGUAUUUAUUAGUUCAGUUCUAAGAGACCUCCUUCUGGGCUUACCCCACUCCUCAGGUACUUCUCUCUCCUUCCUCCUUCUCCUCCACAGUCACAAGUAACCAAGGAACCUGAAAGUGGAUGUGUAGCUAUUUGAAGAAGGCAAGGAACCCUGAGAUUCUUCUUUGAAUCCUCUAGUCCAAGUCUUAGACCAGUGAUUGGUGCUUACCUUGAACAAAAUUUUGUCUGUGUUCCUAAUCCCUUCAAUACUCUGGGUACAAUGCUCCCAAUCACCCUGCACAUUUGAUUCUAAAUGGCUUUUAUUUUUUAAAAAUCCAUAUCCCUAGGACAAGAGAACAGGAUGCCUAUAUCCCCAAAAUGAGCUCCAGGACACUGAUGGGAAUGAUCCCAAAGAUCACCCCACCUCAGAAACGUCUGUGCCAAGAGACUUCCCCAGAUAGAAACACUGGGACAGUGGUUUGAACGACUUCUUUUAUGGUUGUCCAGUUUGCUAUGGAAAUAAAAGGCAUUGAUUUUUUAAAAAGAUGAUUGGAACCUGUCUUUGGCCACAUAGGGCCACUUGGAUCCAUUUCCAGGCCUUACUCAUAUAUUGCCUUCACUGAAGGGCUUUGGCUUUAAGUCCCAGACUGGUCUCCCAAGUGAACCAUAAGUGUUUUGGAGCUCAUCUGGGGUGAGGCAUGAGAAUGUUGCCCCAUCUAUCCCUUCAGGAAAAGGUGCCUUCCCUCCCUUUCUCCUAAAGCCUGGUCCCCAGAAAUUGUUUUUGUCUCCAAAAGUCUAGUAUGGUCUUUAUACACCCAGACUCUUAGUGUUGCGUCCUGCCUUGUUUCCUUGUUAAGGAUCUAUGCAGACCUCCCGCUUUGGCUUAGCUAGCGUGACAUUGGCUAUCAUUUGACAAGACUAACUUUUUUUUUUUUUUUUUUUUGACUGAGUCUCCCUCUGUCACCUAGGCUGGAGUGCAGUGGCACAAUCUUGGCUCGCUGCAACCUUCACCCUUCACCUCCCAGGUCGAAGCGAUUCUCCUGCCUCAGUCUCCCGAGUAGCUGGGAUUACAGGCGUGCGCCACCAAAUCUGGCUAUUUUUUUAUUAUUAUUAUUUUUAGUAGAGAUGGGGUUUCACCAUGUUGGCCAGACUGGUCUUGAACUCUUGGCCUCAAAUUAUCUGCCCACCUCGGCCUCCCAAAGUGCUGGGAUUACAGGCAUGAGCCACCAUGCCCAGCUGACAAGACUAAUUUUUUAUCCCUUGGUUUAUUGGCUUCAACAUCUUCUGGAAUCAGAGGUGAUUUUUUCUUACCUUGGAUGCCUGAGACUAGGGGAGUAUAGAAUUCCAAUUGGUAAUUAAGGCAUCUUUCUGCUCCUGAUCAGAAGGGCAGGUUAGUUGGGAGAGGUCAGAUGGCACAACAGAAGUCACCUUGUAAGUAAGGCAAAGACUUGAAGGCAUUAGCGUUUCUCAUUACUAGGUCAAUAACCUGAGGGAAUCAAUGGCUUUUUGCCGCUCUACCUCUUGUGUAUCUCUUUGACUUUUCUUUCUCUGUCUAGUUUCCUCUGUUCUCAGUUUAUAUUCUAUGUUAUCAGUCUCUCUUUCCACAGUACAAACAUCCAUCCUUUCUCCUGUGCAAUUCUGUCUCUCCCUCUUAUUAUCUUUAUUUGUACUUUUUCCUUCCUCCCUGUCUAGGCAUUGGGCAUGUGCCUCUUCUUAGCCUGUGAUUUUGCCUUGGGACUGAUGAUAAAUUAUUUCCAGAUUCAAUCAGCCCUGGUCCUACCCCAGUCCAAUCAGAAGUAUGUUGGUGGGAAUCAACCUGAUCCUGGCCCUUUCUUCUUCUCCAUUUUCAUUCGUAAUCCCCCUCAGCAGAUCUUUACAAGCAGUUUCCUUAUAGCUCAUGUAUCUUUAGGUCUUUGCCUUCCAAGCACUGUACAGAAUACUUUGUGGUUCCUUUUUAGUCUGACAUUUUGUGGAGCAGUGAAGCGUGCUCAGAGACAUAAUCAGCUGAAGAGAAAAAAUCCACCCAUGGAUUUAUAUCAGCUAAAUACUAAUAAUUGAUUUUGUUUGAUGUGCCCAUAAUUUUUAAAGCUGCAAUAUAAUAUAAUGAGGGACCACAGGUAAUUUCUCCUGUCAUUUGUUUUGGCUGGAUGGGGGUGGGGGAGUAAUUGCUUAAAGUUUUACCAUUACACAUUAAACUCUCUAUAAUAAUCUUGUUUGGGGCUUGCUAACUGUUGAGCUGUUUUAACUAAACUGGUAGGCAAUCGGAGUUGAUUUAAAUGAAAAGAUAAUUUAACAAAUCUAUACUAUAAAAAGAGACAUUUGCUUAAUUGACAUGUAUUUUUUCCUUCUGAGUCACCUAAACAUUUACUCUUGACACCAACUGUUCAUGAUACUGAAUAGACAGUCCAUAUAAGAGAAAUUAGUGGACCUAAAGAAGCCAGAUUGUAGGUGUUAAUUUAUUAAACAGAGUGCAAAGCCCUUGGAAAUGUCACUGCUUGGCAAUACCAUAUGGAAUGCCAAAAUUUACAAUGACUUUUCUUUAUAAGUUAUCCAAAAGGGAUUUGAACAAGUAAGAGGUUAUGCCAAAAUGUCUCCAAUGUAUGGUCCUGUAAUAUAUUGCAGCUUGAAGCCAAUGAUCCCUUAUGACUUGUAUACAACUAAUGCAUGUUUUAUUGAAUUUUGCAUUUCCCACGUGUGGUAAGUUCUUUAAAAUGUUUUUGAUCACCUUUUUGUGCCAUUAAACUUGUACAGAAAAUGUUUUUAUGGCCAUUUUCAAAGGGAGAAAGUUUAAAAUGGAAACAGCCCACCCUUUCUGCCCUAUAGCUGUAGUUAGAAUUGAGUACCUGUAGCAAAACAGCUGUAAUUGGUGGUUGUAGUGUUAGAGGUGUUAGCUUGCUAGUGACUAGCUUUGGAGAGUAAAUGCAUGGUAUUGUACAUCACAUUUCUUAACUCGUUUUAACCUCUGAAAAGAAUAUAUUCUUCUUUGUAGUCCUUCUUCCCACCCCCUUGCCCUCUCCCUCUCCCUGCUCCCAGUUGUCUUACAGUUGUAAAUAUCUGAUUUGAGGCCCAAUAACUCUUGCCAAGUAAAGUCAGCAAACAACAAACAAACCAAAAUGUGGGGAAAAGGCAUUUCUCAACCAUCUCUCAGCAGUUAUUGAUCAUUUCUUAAGGAACAGCAUUGUGAUCAAAGACUCAACUUUACGUAAAAAUCAGUGGUAAAUUGGGGUUGUAUUUGGCCAUUUGAUUACAUUUCAGGAUUGAAUAGUUUUCAGAAUCACAUGUAAUCCAAAGACAGUAGGUAGUGAUGUCCCUUAUCCCUGCAGCUGUUUUAAGAUAGAGACCUCAGAAGACUCUGCUUGACCGAUGACCAAUAAUUAUUUGAAAAAAAAAGAAAAAAUGAGAGAAAUAAAACAGAUAUUUAAGAACUUUAGCCACCUAUUUAGAAUAGUUAUAGCCAGAAAAAAAAACAAGGGCAUGAGUUCAAAUGCAUUACUAUCAGUGUCCUAGGCAAUACCUAACCUACUCUGAAAUUGUGAUUCAAAAGCAGUAUUUCAAGAGGCAUUCUCCUUUUUUGGUUUGCUGACCCCACUUGGACUGGUAGGUUUGGUGAGGCCCCCAUAAACCAGCUGGAGCAGACCCUUUUCAUCUCCUGUGCCUGUAACACCCCUCUUCCCCCACCCCCUCCGCAAUUCAAUGAGGGCUUUCUUGGGUCAGAGGACUUCAAGGUUGUCUAGAGAAGUUUGCCAUGUGUGUAAGGUGCUGUGAACUGUGAGUGCUGAAGAUUCGCAGCAUUCAAUACCAGGCAGCCAAAGAGCUGCUCUUGCAAUUAUUUUGGCUCUCAAGCUCUGUUCUUCAUCGCAUUCUCAUUUCUGUGUACAUUUGCAAGAUGUGUGUAAUGUCAUUUUCCAAAAAUAAAAUUUGAUUUCAAUA